UCUUUCUGAAAGUUAUUGUUAAGCGCCUUCCUUCAUAGAUUCACUGCCUGUCGCUUGAUGUUGUCCGUCUUGGGAGUCUGAAGCUAUGGGUCUUCUCCAGAAAAAACAAAACCGAAAAAACACACAAAGAUCCACACUAAUUAACAUUCCAUUUCAGAGGCUUCGCCGACCAGCCCCAUGGCCUGCGCAAGGGCCCCAAGUUAAGAGAUUUAGUUGUGCAAUAUAUAAGGGAAUGUGAGAUUUGUAAAAUGUUGUUACAGGGUUAUAAAUUAUUAACACCAAAUGAGUAAUAGAAGCAGUGAUUGCUAAAGAAUGUUAAAGUGUGUUGGGAUCACUGUGAACUUCAUGAAGAAAGUGGAACUUAAAAUGAGUGUGUUAAGGGAAGGCAAAUCGGACACAGGGUUCGACAUGAAUCAAGAUCCACAGAGCUGGAAUACCCCCAUGUCUGGCACCUGGCUGGCCGACAUGACCUUUGGCUCUAAAAAGAAGACUCCAUUUUUCAUGAUAAAAUGGCAGUGGUGAAAACCCCCAGCAGAGGACUAAAGAAUGCUAAAGAACCCUUUAAUAAUGCAUCACCCCAUCUCUUGAAGAACCUAGUGGAGGAGCCGAAAAAAAGAAAAGAAGUACCUAAUCACCUCCUAGAAUCAAAGGUUUAUGCAAAACUUGUGAAUAAUAAGGUCAUACAGGCAAGACCUGGCAUAAUACAUUUUGGAGGCUAUCAAGUAGAAAAACAACACCAACAGAUUCUGCAUCUGGUCAAUGUUUCCAAUGAAGACACACGUGUUCAUAUUUUACCCCCGCAAACCAAAUACUUUGAGAUCAAUUAUGUAAGAAAGGAACACCACCUGGUCCCUGGCUUGUCCCUCACGGUCACCGUUACAUUUUCUCCAGAUGAGUGGCGAUACUAUUAUGACUGCAUCCGUGUUCACUGUAAGGGAGAUGACACUUUGCUUGUUCCUAUUCAUGCCUAUCCAGUCAUGAACUCACUAGACUUUCCUUCAUUUAUAAAUCUGUCAAAUGUUCUACUUGGUGAAAGCAAAACUUAUGUUAUUCCUUUGCAGUGCAGCUGCCCUGUAGAUUUUGAGUUUUAUAUCACCUUGAUUCAGUCUCAUCAAGCCUUUGCUAUUGAGCCAACAUCAGGAAUAAUUCCGGCUAAUGGGAAGAUGACUGUGACUAUUAAGUUUACACCCUUUCAGUAUGGGACUGCACAAAUAAAAAUGCAGUUAUGGAUUUCGCAGUUCAACUCUCAACCAUACGAAUGUGUCUUCACCGGAACAUGCUAUCCCAACAUGGCCUUACCAUUAGAAGAGUUUGAAAGGUUGAAUACCCUUUCUAAGAAAGUAAACGUUCCUCCAGAAAAAGCAAUGAUGCAUAUAAAUUUUCACCGACCGCCAGCGAAGCCGAAGCCUCAGAAGGUGAAGGAAAUUGAGUACCAGAACCUCAGAUUUCCAGUAGAUUUAUCGAAUCCAUUUGCUGUGGCAACUGUUUUAAACCAAGAACCAGGAAAAUUGAAGAUUAAAGAAUUAAGAGAAGUUUUGGACCAGGGCACUGAAAUUUCAAAAACGAGACAGAUGAAGGAGGCACUCUUUGAACAGAAAGUCAGACAGGACAUUCACGAAGAGAUGGAAAAUCAUCUUAAGUGGCAGGUGCACCUUGGUAAAGAUCCUAUGUCUUUUAAACUUAAAAAAGAGCUUACUGAAGAGUGGCAAAAAGCAUGUGCCAAAUAUAAGCUAGACAGAGGAGAUCCUAUUUUGGAUGAGGAAUUUCAGCGACUUAAAACAGAAGUUAGCCAUAAACGGGUUGUUCGCAAUCAAGAAGAGAAAAUCAAGGAAUUUCAUCCUACUUUUGAUCCACUCAUUAAUAACACUUGGCUCAGCAGGUCCAGGGCACAAAAACGGUUUCAACAAGUAGCACGCAAGGUCAUGAUUCAGGGACGAUUAUUCAAUAUGCUGAGUGCUGUUCGUGAAAUGGACAAAGAGAGUAUACUGAGAAAGAUUGGCCAAGCAAAACAAUCGAUAGCACAAGAGGCGAAUUUCUUCAAAUUCUUCCUGAGGCGGAUCAGUCAGGAUGAUUAUACCAGCCGGUUCUCUGUGUCGCCCAAGGAGGUGCUGCCCUUCGCUUUCCCAGACUGCAGCCCACCCCAGGACUCCAACGAGUUGGCUCCUGAUGGCCUUGGACUGGUCCCAAUUAAGUCUUCAGAAGUUCAAAUCAAGCAGAGUUAUUCCUUCUUCAAUCUGCAGGUUCCUCAACUGUACAAAAUUAAGAGAUAUCAGCCAUUCUCUGUCCACAAGUCUUCAACAAGUUACAGACCUCAAAAGCUUGCCCGAGCCCUAAAGCAAGGAGCUGAGGAUGAAGUCACCACCAUCACAGCCCUUCCGAAACAGGACUCCACAACUCAGCUCUCUGGCAAAACAUCAGUCUUGAGCAUGAAACCACCUGAGGCCUUAGCCAUGUCUCUAGAUUAUGAUCCUCUGUAUGUUUUUAAUCCCAACCCAGGAUUAUUUGCUGUAAUGCAUCCUCUGACCUAUGCAGAAACGUUGAUAGAUUACCAUCUAUGCUCUCACCCCAAGUACAAAUUCACCAAAGAGUCCCGCCACGGGUCCAGCAUUCCUGUCACCCAAAAGCAGUUUCUCCAUCACACGGACAUUAUUCCCGGAAUAAUGCACUGGAAAAGCUUCCAGUCCCUGGUUCUCUCCUCCCUGCCGGACCCCUCCAAGAUGGAGACCACAAAGAGCUGCGAUUCCUUCAAUUCAUUUAUGCUUCCGAUAGACGUCCCUGCCAUCCUUGAUGCCUUACCAGAAGAGGACAGACUAGAAACAGUAGAACGUGAGCUCUGUGAGCAGAAUGUAGAAGUUAUGUUGACUCCAGAAAUGAUCAAAGUGGAAUUCCCUAUGUUGAACUACAAGGACAUCAGGAAGGAGAACCAGAAGCCAACAGAGUCCUCCCUGCCAGACACCCAGAGCCUGGACAGACAGGGACGGAACAAAAAGAACACAUCAGCAGUGUCCCAUUUCCCCCUGAAGACUGUUCUUUAUUUGGUUUCUGGCAAACAUUUAUUUUCAUGGAUGCAAAGAAUCAUCUGCUCUCACUCAAUGGCUGAAAUUCACCAGAGAGAUUCUCUGCUGCCUGGACAGCGGUCUUGGCCCUUUCAAGACCCACAGGGGAAUCACAUUCCCCACAAAAUGUUCAAGGAACUGUGAGACUGUGACUUUAGUUGCUGACACAUUUUUCAGCACUCCUUAGAUCAACACAGUAUUACUCAAUCAUUAGUAUCUCUAAGGGGAGACAGGAUCUAUAUAUUUUUAGACAUGAUUCCAUAAAAUGGUACCAAUUAAUUUCUUUAAUUAUGUGCAUUAGGGAACAUCUUAAUUCUCCAUUUUCAGGUAUUUCUGGUUUUCCAAAACUGUCAGCCAUUUGCCAAACAUGUCACCCUCUUUUCAAAAAUGUCUCAGAAGCACUUUAUUUUAUAUUGGAUUUAUAUUGCCCAAGCAGAUUAUAUAGCUGAGUUCACAGUCUUUGAACAAGACAUAUGGCCUUUUAACCAAAACACUCGUCAUUUCCUCCCACAUAUCUGGAUGCUGGUGAGCACCAUGACAGUCUCUGAGCCGAGUCUCCAUCUUAACCCUUGGCCCCAGCCCACCAAGAGGCAAGCUGGCCCCUAAGAAGCCCAGGUCCUCCCCAUCUCUCCGCCCUUUGUCUACUCCCACUGCACCCAUCAAUUGAUAGCCUCAUUUUACACCACGUCCAGUCAAAGUUCUACCCAGCAACCCCCGCCACACCAACAUCAGCCUCGGCUCCACUCAGCCACUACUUGGUCCAGGUGCACAACUCUCCCUGAGGUGCUCACUCUUCUGGAGCCAUUGCCAGAGUUAGAAAUAGUGUGUAUCUACCUCAUUCAUAAAGAUGAAAAACCAGCCAGCAUUGACUGAGCACUUAGAAGACCUCACACCAGGAUCUCUGUGAAUAAGAUCUCAUUUCACCUUUGCUACAAUGCUGGGAGAUGGGAAUUACACCAUUCGCACAUCAGGAAACAGGGGCUGUGGAUUCUUGGGUAACUUGCCCAUGCUCAGAAACUGAUGCAGCUGAGGCCAGAAGCCAGGUUUGAAUCAUUCAUAAGCUGAGUGUUUUCACUGGUAAGUAAACUAUCACUAACUGUGGUGAAAACCUUCUUUGUAUAUUAAACGAAAUGCUCCUCCGACCUUCACC